AUGAAGAGGGAGAAUCAGAGCAGUGUGUCUGAGUUCCUCCUCCUGGACCUCCCCAUCUGGCCAGAGCAGCAGGCUGUGUUCUUCACCCUGUUCUUGGGCAUGUACCUGAUCACGGUGCUGGGGAACCUGCUCAUCAUCCUGCUCAUCCGGCUGGACUCUCACCUUCACACCCCCAUGUUCUUCUUCCUCAGCCACUUGGCUCUCACUGACAUCUCCCUUUCAUCUGUCACUGUCCCAAAGAUGUUAUUAAGCAUGCAAACUCAGGAUCAAUCCAUUCUUUAUGCAGGGUGUGUAACUCAGAUGUAUUUUUUCAUAUUUUUCACUGAUCUAGACAAUUUCCUUCUCACUUCAAUGGCAUACGAUCGGUAUGUGGCCAUCUGUCACCCCCUCCGCUACACCACUAUCAUGAAAGAGGGACUGUGUAACUUACUAGUCACUGUGUCCUGGAUCCUCUCCUGUACCAAUGCCCUGUCUCACACUCUCCUCCUGGCCCAGCUGUCCUUUUGUGCUGACAACACCAUCCCCCAUUUCUUCUGUGAUCUUGUUGCCCUACUCAAGCUCUCAUGCUCAGACAUCUCCCUCAAUGAGCUGGUCAUUUUCACAGUGGGACAGGCAGUCAUUACUCUACCACUAAUAUGCAUCUUGAUCUCUUAUGGCCACAUUGGGGUCACCAUCCUCAAGGCUCCAUCUACUAAGGGCAUCUUCAAAGCUUUGUCCACCUGUGGCUCUCACCUCUCUGUGGUGUCUCUGUAUUAUGGCACAAUUAUUGGACUGUAUUUUCUCCCCUCAUCCAGUGCCUCCAGUGACAAGGACGUAAUUGCCUCUGUGAUGUACACGGUGAUCACCCCAUUGCUGAAUCCCUUCAUUUAUAGCCUAAGGAACAGGGACAUAAAGGGAGCCCUGGAGAGACUCUUCAACAGGGCAACAGUCUUAUCUCAAUGA